AACGGCCCCAUCCGGCGCCGGCGGCGGGUGCCCGGCGGUCUUUGCUGCCGCCCGGGGGCGCAGAGGCCGGGCCUUUUCUUUCAGCACAAACGUCAGUUUGUAAAAGGGAGGUGCUGGAGUCUGAGGAGUUUUCAGGCUUCCGUCUCGAAGGAAGUCUGGCAGGCUCGGAAUUGUCAUCUUCCUCAGGCAAAUAGUUUUUCACCUUAGAGCCAGCAAGGCCAAACCGCCCAGUCACCCGACUUCCCACAGUCUCAGCAGGGAGGAAUAAGUUUUUUUCAUCUGUAAUUUGGAAGCCAAGUCAGUAACAAAAUGAAACCAGUAAAGCAUCUGUUGACCACCAGUAACAAAUCGGCAAAUGUUCCAGCAUUAACUACUAAAAAAGGACUACAUAAUUUACCAUUAUCACCUGAGCUAAAGGAAAAACAUAAUGCAAAAUUAAUUCAUGAUAAAAUUGAACCAAUGGUCCUAAGAUCUCCACCAACAGGAGAAUCCAUUUUACGGUAUGCUUUGCCCAUUCCAUCGAGUAAGACAAAGAACUUACUACCAGAAGAUGAAAUGAUCGGAAAAAUUAUCAAACAUCUGAAGAUGGUUGUUUCCACUUUGGAAGAAACCUAUGGACAUUGCGAUCAGAAUGGAGAAGAACCAUUUGUAAAGCAUGAACAUGAAGAAUUAUCUUUAUCUGUUGGGGAUGAUAUGAAUUCAUUCUUGACAUAUUGUUCGCAAUUUGCAGCUCAGCUAGAAGAAGCACUUAAAGAAGAACAAAAUAUUUUGGAAUCUCUUUUUAAGUGGUUUCAGUGGCAGGUCAAUCAGAUGGAAGAAAUAAGUAAAGAUCAAACUCUUUUACAAGCAGAGCCUCCAAAACCUGACAAAACAGUCAUUUUAAAUAUUGCAGAAAUAGUAAGGCUUGUACAAAGAUUUGAAGAACUGAAGAAUCGCCUUAAACAGAGGUCUAAAUCCUCCGUGAAAGUCAUGUUGUCUAAAACUAUGGAUAAAGAAAAUCGACCAGAAGCAGUGAAAAGUUGUGAAGCUCUGGCACAGAAAAUUGAAGAAUUCUUAGAAGCCCACUCAACUGAUGAAUUUAAAGAUGUUUCUGCAACAGAACCACAAACUGCUCAUUCAAUGACUAAUCGAUUUAAUGCCAUGUUGAAAGUAUUUGAAAACCAGGCAAAUAUGUUGGAGAGAGCUGUAAAUGAUCAAGUUUUGUUAGAUGCUGAAUACAAACAGAUGCAGUGUGAUUUUCAGUUGUUAUCAGAAGAGAAGUUGGUGCUGGAAAAUGAACUACAAAAGUUGAAGGACAAAGAGAAAACUAAGCCUACAAAUAAUCGAACAAAGAAAGCUGUGAAAACAGUGAAGAAAAAAGACAAAGGAAAAUCUGAGGAUUCAGAAAAGAAGAUGUCUCCAGAAAAAGAGUUUAAAAUAAAAGAAGAUUUGGAUCAAGUACAGAAAGUAGCACGUCUGGAAAUUGAGAACAAAGUCCUUCAGGAGCAAUUGAAACAGGCUUUACAGGAAGCUGAAAAAGCUAAGCAUCAACUUAACUAUUUCCUAAAUCAAGAGAAGUUACUUAAAAGUGAGGGGAAAACUGAGACAACAAUGCAAGUGGGUAAUAGUCAAACAAAAGUUAAAGGUGAAGAUUCAAAAAAUAUACCAUUGGAGAAAGAAACAAGAAAAUCACUGGUUUCAGAUUCAGGUGGACAAAGGACAAGUGAUAAAAUCCAAGAAUAUCCACAGAUCACUGCCCAAAGCGGAAGACUGAUUGAAAAGAGCUCAGAGAAGAAACGAUCUAGCCCUGCUAUUUCAGAUCUUUCACAGAUCCUUAAGUCUCAAGAUGAAUCAGCAUUUUUAGAGAGUUCAAAUGAAGUUUCAGUUGCUGAAAACCAAUCCUAUAAAUCUCCAUCAGAGACCCAUGAUAAAUCACUUACAACAGUAUCAUCCAGCAAAGAAGUUCAAGAUUCACUGUCUGUUGGAACAUUGGCUCAAAAAAACGAAACAGUGAUAUCACCAUUCAUUUUACCUCCUGUUCUUACAGAAAGUAAAAAGGCUGAUGUUUCAGAAGAACAAUUACAAAAGAUGACUGAAGAACAAACUUACCAAGCAGCAGAAAAAUCUCAAGCUGACAGUGAAGUUCCAGAUGAAAAUCUUAUGGUUGAAAAUAAAGAUUCAGUAACAAAAGUCCAAAUAGAACAAAUGAAACAAAGAACUUCUAGUAUGGAAAGACAUGAGGAGACUCUUACAACCCCACAAUUGCCUGAGGACAUGGUUUUAGUUUCAAGAAUCCAAUCUGAAACUAAAAAUCUUAAAGCUACCAGAAAUGAGAGUUUUCAUUCUCAUAAUGAUGUACCAGAAGAAAAUCUUAUGCUUGAACAAGACACAAAGUCAAAAACGGAAGUAGAAGUAAAGAAACAAAAAUCUUUCCAAGAUAAUCAACUCAGUACUCAUAAUGAAGUACCAAAUGAAAGGCUUGUAGUUGAGCAUCAAGAAUCAUUGUCAAAAACCAAAUUACAAAUAAAGAAACAAGAAACUUCUACAGAGCAACCACUCACCACUCCUGAUAAAGAACCAAAUGAAAAUCUUAUACUUAGGCAUCAAGACUCAAUGUCAAAAUCAGAAAUGCAAGUGAAGGAACAAAGAACUCUCAAAGGGCAAAGAAUUAUUACUCAUGAUGAAGAACCAGGCAAAAAUCUUGUGCUUGAACAUCAAGAUUCAGUGUCAAAACUGGAAAUGCAAAUUGAAAAAACCAAAAAACUUCCUAGAGAGAAAAGACAUAGUACUCAUGAUGAAGAAUCAGGUGAAAAUCCUAUGCUUAAACAUCAAGAUUCAGUGUCAAAAAUCCAAGUGCAAUUAGAGAUUCAAGAAACUUCUGAAGGAGAAGGACGUAGCAUACCAGAUAAAAAUUCUAUGUUUGUUCAUCAAGAUUCAGUGUCAAAACUCCAAAUGCAAGAAAAGAAAAAAAUAACUCCUGGAAGGGAAAGGCGUAAUACUCGUAUUGUAGUACCAAAUGAAAAUGUGAUUUCUGUUCAUCAAGAUUCAAAGUCAAAACUCCAAAUGCAAGAAAAGAAACAAAUAAAUUCUGGAGUGGAAAGACACAAGACGUUUCCUUUAGAAAUCAAAAAAAAGGAUAUAUCACUUGAACAUCUGUUGCCUGAGGAGAAAGUUUUAUUAUCAAGAAGCGAAUCUCAAACGAAGAAACUUCAAGCUAAAGUAACUUCAAGAAAAAGAAAACAAUUGACUUUUGAGGAGAAGACCCAAGAUGGCUGACCAGACACAGCCAGGAAGAGCAUCUCCCACUGAGAGACCAGACCAUCAAGAAGACGGACACACUCUGAGCAUGUCUUUGGAAGGACGGCAUUGAGAGUGGACAGAGGGAGGAUGUAGACCCUGGGCUGAAGGAGUAGGAAGCUGGGAAGCCUGCACAGGGCUGCCAAGCAUCAGGACUCAUUCUUGGUCCCCAGAAAUUUUUGGGGAAAGGGUGAGUUAAAUAGGUGAGGAGUGGUCUUAUCUCACCAUGCACCUCCAGAAUCCUAGCUGCAGAAGACCCUAUUGUCCUGAUAGACAUUUGAGCUGGCAGGGAGAGCUGCUUUAAGAGGUGGCAGGGACAGGGGUCUAGGCUGUGUGGAUUCCAGAGGGUUUGGCGCUGCAAUGACUACAGUGGAGCAUGGCCAGCGAUGCCCAUCCCUCAAGGCUUGCCAUGCUUCUCUAGGUGGCUUUGACCUUUGUUAACUGUCAGGCCUGGACAAAGCAGAGCUGUCAGUGACAUCGGGCCAAUCUUAUCUGCACACCUCCCUGUCUGCCAGCCUCUCCUGGGGUCCCUGCCUGGCUAUGUCUACUUGCAACACAGUCUCCAAUGCCCAAUUGUGGUGCUUCCUGGUGGCCACUGCCAUGGUGCCUUUGCCAGCAGACCUCGGCUAACCAUCAGAAAGCUUCUGCAGAGGGACCCCACCAAUGUGCACCCACCUGCAGCCUCCUCGCACCACUUUGUCAUUGUGCACUAACUUUCAGCCUCCCCUCAAUGCUUUGCCAGCAUGUGCACAUGGAUGCCAUCAGGCCACAGCUGGCAUGCGCACACAAGGACCCCAUAGCACCACUGCUGGCAUGCAUCUGCAGACAGCACUACGCUGCUGCCUUGUCACAGCCAGCACAUGCACAUGUGCAGAAUCCACAGUGCUGCUGCCUAGUCACCACUGGCACAUGCGGGGACCCUGCUGUCACCACCACCCUGACAAAGCACUUUGCUGGGACCCCCCCAACUGAGUGUUGUUGCCAGCAGACUGGGAGACCCUUGGCCCCUGCAAGCAUAGCAGGUGUUUAACCUCAAGGAGCCAGAGAGAAAAGCCACAGGCCUGGCCCCAUAGGAAGAAGAUUGAAACUGGACCCCCCUUCCUUUCACCACAUGUAAAAAUCAACCCAAGAUGGAUCAAAGACUUAAAUGUAAAACCUACAACUAUAAAAACCCUAGAAGGAAACCUAGGAAAUACCCUUCUGGACACAUGCCCUGGCAAAGAUUUCAUAACAAAGACCCCAAAAGCAUUGCAACAGAAACAAAAAUUGACAAGUGGAAUCUAAUUAAAUUAAGGAGCUUCUGCACAAGAAAAGAAACUAUCAACAGAGUAAAGAGACGACCUAUAGAAUGGGAGAGAAUAUGCACAAACUAUGCAUCCAACAAAGGUCUAGUAUCCAGCAUCUAUAUGGAACUCAAAUCAAUAAGCAAAAAACAACCCCAUUAAAAAAUGAGCAAAAGACAUGAACAGACACUUCUCAAAAGAACACAUACAUGCGGCCAACAAGCAUAUGAAAAAAAUGCUUAACAUCUCUAAUCAUUAGAGAAAUUCAAAUCAAAACCACAAUGAGAUACCAUCUCAUACCAGUCAGAAUGGCCAUUGUUAAAAAGUAAAAAAUAACAGAUCCUAGUGAGGUUGUAGAGAAAAGGGAAGGCUUAUACACUGCUGGUUGGAAUGUAAAUUAGUUCAGCCACUCUGGGAAGCAGUUUAGAGAUUGGUUCUCAAAGAACUUAAAACAGAGCUACCAUUUGACCCAGGAACCCCAUUACUGGUUAUAUAGCCAAAGGAAUAUAAAUCAUCCUACCAUAAAGACACAUGCAUGUGCAUGUUCAUCACAGCACUAUUGACAAUAGCAAAGACAUAGAGUCAACAAAGAUGCCUAUCAACAGUGGACUGGAUAAAGAAAAUGUGGUACAUAUAUAUCAUAGAAUACUAUGCAGCCAUAAAAAGAAUGAACUCAUGUCCUUUGCAGCAACAUGGACAGAGCUAGCAGCCAUUAUCCUAAGCAAAUUAAUGCAGGAACAGAAAACCAAAUACCACAUGUUCUCACUUAUAAGUGGGAGCUAAAUAUUGAGCUCACAUGAACACAAAGAAGGGAACAAUAGACACUGGGGCCUACUUGAGGGUGGAGAAUGGGUGGAGGUGAGGAUCAAAAAACUAUCAGGUAAUAUGCUGUCACUACCUGGGUGACAAAAUAAUUUGUACACCUAACUCCCAUGACACACAAUUUACCCAUCUAACAGACCUCCACAUGUACCCAAAAUAAUAGAAAAAAAAAGUAAAACAUGUAACUUUUGUACAUUAACCUUGUAUCCUGCAACCUUGCCAUAACUGCUAGUCUGACAAUUCCAACAUCCCUGUUGUAUCUGAAUUUAGUUGUAAUGCUUGCUCUGUCUCUUCACUUUUUUUUGUCUGUUAGUGUGCAUUGUAAUAUUUUAUUAAAAGCCAGACAUGAUAUACUAGGAAAAGAAACUCCAGUAAAUGGGUCUCUAAUUUUGUGGCGAAUAAGUAUGAGGGAAAAAAAGUCUUCUAUAAUCUUAUGGUUAGAUCUCAAUCUUUUGGUGAUCCUGUGUCCCUGGACUAUGAACUUCUCCAGUGCUUCUCAGUUUUUUCCCUUCUUAUGUGGGGCAGGAUGGCUAGACGGGGCUGGAGUUGGGUAUUUCCCUUCAUGUAGGCUUGUUAGGCUCUGAUAAAACCCUAGUCGGUUUGGCUCUGGUAAAAAGUACGUGUCCUGAGAGCAGACCUUGUUAAGAAGAACAGACUGCUCUGGCAUAUUUUGAAGUGGUUCCUUUUUCCUUUCCCUCUCUUAGGAACAUAAAGGGAUUUUUUUCUCCACUAUUCAUUGUGAGAACCUGGUACAGCUCCUGGAGGCAAAACUCACAAAAGUGUGGAAACUCCCUAUAACUGAGCCUCCUUGGUGGUUUUAUCCUUCAGACGUGUCCUCACUGAGGUUCCAGCAAUUCACUAAUUGCAAUUCAGGUUUUCUUAUCCUGGUUAAAAAGGUUUCUGCUUCAUUAAGUUGUGAUUCCCUAUCUUUACCUGUUUCUCCAGUUUUGGGGGCAGCAGUUUGCCCUGUGACGUCUUUUCUAUGAAGUAUCUAAGAAGAGUUAUUUUUCAACUUGUUCAGCUUUUUACUUGUUGUUAGGAUGGAGUGACAGUUUCUGAGAUUUUUACAUGUUAGACUGGAAAUUGGAAGGUCCGUUUAAAAAAUUUUUUAUCUUCCUUACCUCAGAAAAGGUAUUUAUCUCUUCAUUGCUCUCUUUUGGACUGGUGACUUAUAGCAUCCUUCCAUUUGUGUCAGUCAUUUAUCUUAUUUUAAUAAUUUAAACUUUUUUCUAAAAUAUGUAUACCAUAAGAGAAUCAAGUAAUAAAUUCAUUUGUUUAAUAACUAGGUAUAUCUAUGAAAUAGCAGAUUUUCACGUAUACACUGAGGAGAACUAUUGUCUUUAUUUUUAUGCUUUAAGUAUGUACUAUAUUUUAAUAUGUCAGUGCAACUUACUGUGGACAUGUGAUUGUUACAAAAAUUAGAGAAAAUAUUUUUGUCCAGUUAAACAAUAUAUAGUUUGUCUUUCUUUUAUAGUGAACUACAAAAGUAUCUCUUGUUCAGAACUUGAAUAUGUAUUGAAUGAAAUACCAAAAUGAAAAUAUUUGAGAGCAAGUAUUCUUUUUAAAGUUUACUUUUUAAACAGUGUUUACUACAAAAUAUGUUACAGGUAAUUUCAUAAGACUUACGUGUAAAUUUUAACAAAUAAGCAUGAAGCAAAACUAGGAUAACCACCACUUAGGUCAAGAAAUAGAGUUCUACUCUCACAUAAAAUCUUCAGUGUAUCUCUCACAAUUUCCUCCAUCCUCACAGUGGCAAUAGUUAUAUUGAUUUUAAGAUAACAGUUUUCUUGUUUCCUCUUAUUUUGGUCAAAACAUAUGUAAUUGCCAAUAUUCAACUAUUUUUGACCUAUAAGAAAAUGACAAAUUCAUGUGGUUCAACCUAAUAGUUUUACCAUUUCAGUAUGUAAUUAUAAUAUAAUUUUUGAAGAUUUUAAGAAUAAAUAAUUCUCUAAAUAUC